GCAGACCCGGGGCGCCCAUGGAGUUGGCGUCGGAGCAACAGCUGCGCGGGCGGAGCAGAAAGCAAGUGAUUGCUUUCCUUUCCUCAUUUUUGGAAGCCCUGCCUAACACACAGCUGCACUGUACAUCCCAGUUCCUGGAUGGACGAAGAAAGUGAACUGAUCCAGCCCCAAGACCAGAGCUGCUGGGCCUUUCUGCCCGAUUUGUGUCUGUGCCGUGUUUUCUGGUGGCUAGGAGACAGGGACAGGUCCAGGGCUGCUCUUGUCUGCAGAAAGUGGAACCAGAUGAUGUAUUCUGCUGAGCUCUGGCGGUACAGAACCAUCACCUUCAGCGGGAGACCUUCCAGGGUACAUGCAUCUGAAGUUGAGUCAGCUGUUUGGUAUGUUAAGAAGUUUGGUCGUUAUCUGGAGCACCUGGAGGUCAAAUUCAUGAAUCCUUACAAUGCUGUCUUGACCAAGAAGUUCCAGGUCACCAUGCGGGGCCUCCUGUCUUGUCUGAGUAAGAGCAACAACCGUCUGAAAUCUCUUUCCAUCCAAUACCUGGAGCUGGACCGCCUGGUAUGGAGGAACAGCAUCAGGAGCUCAUUCAUCAGCAGCUUGAGCUUCUUCUUAAAGAAGAUGGGCAAACGCCUGGAUUAUCUCAACCUAAAAGGGGCCAGGCUGACCGUGGAGCAAGGCUGCCAAAUUCUCGACUCCCUCAGCUACAUGAGGAAUGAGAAUGUGAUCUCAGAGCUCAACAUCGAGGACUAUUUCAGCCAUCACCUUGCUGUCUACAACAGCCCCCAGUUCAAAAAGACCAUGUCCACAUUCCACAAUCUUGUGUCCCUGAACCUCAACUACAACUGUAUCUCCGACGAGCUGCUUGAGAACUUGUGUGAGAAUGCCAGCACCCUCCGGACCAUCAACAUCAAAUGCCACGUUCAUGACCCCCACGGACAGGUCAUCUGGGGUAUGUCCUGGGCCAAGCUGGCCAGGCAGGCCACCAAUCUGAAGGUGAACUUCUUCUUUGAACGGAUCAUGAAGUACGAACGCUUGGCCCGAAUCCUCUUGCAGGAGAUCCCGAUCAGGAGCAUCAGUCUGAGAAGCUGCUAUUUCAGUGACCCAGACUGUUCAAUGAGACCCACUCUGAUAGAUCUCCUGCCCACCUUCCGGCACACUCUGCAGAAAUUAACUUGUGAAUUCAACAACAACCAUGAGUCACUCGACGAGGAGCUGCACCUCCUCAUCAUAUCCUGCAGGAAGUUGUUUUACUUCAAAAUCUGGGCUUUCCUUGAUGUUAGUUUUGUGGAGCGGAUCCUGAAGAGUCAGAAAGAACGGCAGUGUGCCCUGCGUGUAUUCAAGGCGAGAAUUUAUACAAACAGAUAUGAGACGAAUGAAGAGGACAAGACCCUGCAGGAAAUUUACAGGAAGUACAGAAAGCUGAUCGAAUCAGAGCUUAGCUAUUUUGUCAUCGUUUACUCUGUGAUGUAAUGAGCACUCUACAGAUGAAGAAAGCUGGGAGCACUUUGAACUUGAAAAUCAUUUCUCUUAGAACUACACUUGGGCACUGCCGGCCCUUUUGCUCCUCUCUCUCCCCUCCACUUUUUUUUUUUGUCAGCUCCAUGACAACAUGACCAGCUCAGCAAAGGCUGAGACUGCCCAUGACCUGAAGGCUCCAGGUGGCUUUAAAGCGCUAUGUUUACCAACUA